AGACUGGGCCCCGUACAUGAAUGAGAAGGAAGGUAUUCCUUAAUUCUCCGGCACGAACGCCAACAGCGUUGCUUUCUUCGGUGUCACAGUUCUUAGGCAAACAGCAGUGAAUAUUUACGCAAUGUGGGAAAGUUUCCUAAGUGGAGCUGCCGGUUUUUCAAGUAGUUGAACUACUUUCGUGUGUGUGUGUGUGUGUGUGUGUGUGUGUUUCCCAUUCAUCAACUUUGGAGUUUGGCUCUAACACCUCACUUGAAAACAGAAAACAAUUUCCUAGCUUAUUCAGUGGCAGUUUUUGCCGCUCUCUCUCCUUUUCUAAGGUUCAGGAUUUUAAAACUUAUGUAGAUCAGGCAUGUAGAGCUGCUGAGGAGUUUGUCAAUAUUUACUAUGAGACAAUGGAUAAAAGAAGACGGGCACUAACCAGGCUGUAUCUGGACAAGGCCACCUUAAUAUGGAAUGGAAAUGCUGUUUCAGGGCUGGAUGCCCUAAAUAAUUUUUUUGACACAUUGCCUUCUAGUGAGUUCCAGGUCAAUAUGUUAGAUUGCCAACCAGUUCAUGAGCAAGCAACUCAGUCCCAAACUACAGUUCUUGUUGUGACCAGUGGAACUGUGAAGUUUGAUGGAAACAAACAACAUUUCUUCAACCAGAACUUCCUGCUGACUGCUCAGUCCACUCCCAACAAUACUGUGUGGAAGAUUGCAAGUGAUUGCUUCCGUUUUCAAGAUUGGUCUAGUAGUUAAAGGGGCAAAAGUCCAUUCUCAUUUGGUCCAUUAGUUCCAGCAAUUGAAAUUUAUGUGAAUUAUUUUGAUUGUAGAAGCACUAUAAUAUGUGCUGAAACUAAAUUUCUUUAAUAUUUUCUAUUCCUGUCAGCACCUUUUCUAGCAGCUGCCAGUUUGGAGCAUUGCCCUCUAAGAGCUUUAAAACUAUUUUUUUACAUGCCUUAUAUACAUUCCACUAAUGACAUUCUUAUAAUAAUAUUAAACACAUGAUCUUGGUACUAACAUACUCACUGUGAACCCAGCCUAUUGCAAAAAUAAAAUCUUUUUAUAAUAUUAUCUAUGGGAUGUCAGCACAAUAUAACACUCUGGGAAGAAGUGGAGUUUUUUGGUUAUUAGGUUAAUUUUCUAGUAAAACACGUUGCCUGUUUUCAGUUAACACUGGUAAUGCCAUUUUAAUAUAUGGCUUUUUCAAAUCAGUUCAGUGAAAAUAGUACAGAUUUAGGUUUACAUAACUACUCUGACAUACUGGAAUUGCAUAUAGAGAUGUUCAGUGGUCGUUUUUCAUUUUAAGUAAUUUUUGUUUUGGCAUUUUUUUGUGUGAAGUAAAUUAAUCAACUAGAGAGGUGCAAAACGUUCUCAGUUGAUAUCUGAGUAUUGGGUGCAUUUGGUGGCUUAAAAGCAAAGCUUCCUAAAAAGAUUUUUCUUGGCAGCUCCAGGUCUAUACAUUUAGGUAAUGAAUGGUAGUAGAACUAAUAGCUUUAACAGGAGAAUAGGGAAUGAGAAAUAGAAAUCCAAGGCUGAAGCCAAAAGUAAGGAGGGUGGCCAAAUGGUAAACUAUUGGUACUUGUUUUCUACCUCCUAAAAAUGUAGCUUAUUUUUAGGAUUUAAAUCACUAAGUAAAUAAGUAUCCUUGCCAAGUGAUCAUGAGUGUCAUUUUUGUUCUAAGACUAAUAUUUUUAGAUCUUUUUACUUCACCUCAUACUUAUCACCAAUGUAUAUCUCCAUUUAUUCAAUAACUUACUGGGGUAAAAUAACAGCAAUAAACCUAACCUUUUAACAGGGUCUAACAUGAGAGUUGGAGUCAAAGCCAUUGUUAUCUUUUGGUGACACCCUUAAAUUUUAAGUCUUCCAGUCUUCCAUGUGAACUUUAGGCCCAAAGUUUCUUAUGUAUCACACAUCCCCCAAAUAAGUGAUUUUUUCCCAGUGCUUUGUACUGUCAACUGCAUUAUCUUUAAUUAUUUAAAGGUAGAAUUAUUUAAUUUUGUGAUUUGUUCUUCCAUAUGACAUUGAGCAAAUAGAUCUGUUUCAAAAUAUGUUCCCGCUAUGUGGAUAACUCUUCUUUUUAAAAAGAAAAUAGAGAAUAGCAAAUCUUCAUGAUAAUCCUCAAAAGAACAAAAUGCUUAACUUUAUCUCUUAAUUUCUAAAGGUAAAUAACCUAGGUUCAGCUUUUGCUUAAACAUUAAAUAUCUUUUCCAUUUUUUAAUGUUUGUAAGCUAGAUAUGCCAGCUUUGUUUCUACAUUGCAACCAAAAACUGUUUCUUUUCACUUAAUUAUAAAACCAGUAAUUCAUUUACUCUUGCCCAAAACUAUACACUGUAUUUCUGUUAUAGUAACAAAAUAGAGUUAUGUAGAAUUGUAUGGAACUCAAAUUUAAACCAUGCUUUCUUGUAGUACUGAUUGAAACUUACACGUUUUAUUCUACUCAUAGUGAGCUUAUUCUUAUUUUGGAUUGAUUUUCCAAAACCACAGCUUCAGCAGCAACAAUCAGAAUGUCCAAAUGCUGUCCUUUCCCUUACAGAGAAGAACAAUGGUAACUAAAAGCUGCAUAUAACUAGCAAUAACUACAUUGAACGGUGUGCAUUGUUCAUGAUUGUUGUGUUUUAAGACUUGUAUAUAAACUGCUUUUUCCAAACUCUGUAUAACUUUUAAAUGGCUGGAACUACUCGUAUAAGGACUAGACUGUAUUUUUGACAUGCUCCUAUUUUUGUAACUUGAAAAAAUAAAAUUUUGCCUUGUGACAGAUUUUCUCAA